AGCAGUUUCUUCCGACAGUUGUGUUGUGCCAAUGGUGGAGAAGAAAACUUCGGGUAUGUGAGCCCCCGCGGUUCGCCCCCUUCCCCUUCCCAAGUCAGUCCUAGAAUUUUCUUACCUAGUCAUUCCUCUUUUUUGGUCUCGCUCUUUCGCCUAGGCUGGAGUGCAGUGGCAUAGUCAUAGCUCACUGCAGCCUCGAUUUCCUGGGAUCAAACCAUCCUCCCACCUCAGCCUCCGGAGUGGCUGGAACUGCAAGCAUGAGGCCCCACGCCUGGUUAAUUUUUAAUUUGUUAUGUGGUGACGGGCUCUCGCUAUGUUGCCCAGUUCGCUCCCAGGACCCCGGGCAGCGGCGGGUGCUGGACCGGGCUGCCCGGCAGCGUCGCAUCAACCGGCAGCUGGAGGCCCUGGAGAAUGACAACUUCCAGGAUGACCCCCACGCGGGACUCCCUCAGCUCGGCAAGAGACUGCCUCAGUUUGAUGACGAUGCGGACACUGGAAAGAAAAAGAAGAAAACCCGAGGUGAUCAUUUUAAACUUCGCUUCCGAAAAAACUUUCAGGCCCUGUUGGAGGAGCAGAACUUGAGUGUGGCCGAGGGCCCUAACUACCUGACGGCCUGUGCGGGACCCCCAUCGCGGCCCCAGCGCCCCUUCUGUGCUGUCUGUGGCUUCCCAUCCCCCUACACCUGUGUCAGCUGCGGUGCCCGGUACUGCACUGUGCGCUGUCUGGGGACCCACCAGGAGACCAGGUGUCUGAAGUGGACUGUGUGAGCCUGGGCAUUCCCAGAGAGGAAGGGCCGCUGUGCACUGCCCGGCCUUCAGAAAGACAGAAUUUCAUCACCCAAUGCAGGGGGAGCUCUUCCUGGACCAAGGGAGGAGCCGCUCAUUCACCCAACAAAACUGUGUCUUAUCUGCCAGGAAAGACCAGCCUCACUCCUGGGAACUGUCUGGCAGGUAGGCUGGGCCCCCCAGUGCUGUUAGAAUAAAAAGCCUCGUGCCGGAA